ACACGGAAACUGGCGCGCUCCAGGGGUGGGGCCCAAACUCAGUUCCACCCUCUGGCUCCCAGCCGAACACCGAACCGGGACCGAUCCGGCCCCGGCUUGAACUAGCUCAGCUCCGAGCUCGCGGAACCACGCCCCCGGGAGACUCUGGCCCGGCCAGCGCGGGCCAGGUCUUCAGUCCUAUAUCGCCCCGCCUUGGGAAAAGGUGCAGGGGCCUCUCGCCGCCUCGUCGGGCCCUUCCUCUCUACCUGCCUCUCCAACCCCUCUCGGCCCCGAGCCACCCGGCAGCGGGGGUGGGUGUGCAGAGGUGCGGCGUCCAGAACCCGGCUCCUGCAGAGGCUCUGGGUGGCAGCAGCCCUGUUACCGCUUAGAUGGCGCGCAGGACAGAGCCCCCCGACGGGGGCUGGGGAUGGGUGGUGGUGCUCUCAGCGUUCUUCCAGUCGGCGCUUGUGUUUGGGGUGCUCCGCUCCUUUGGGGUCUUCUUCGUGGAGUUUGUGGCGGCGUUUGAGGAGCAGGCAGCGCGCGUCUCCUGGAUCGCCUCCAUAGGAAUCGCGGUGCAGCAGUUUGGGAGCCCGGUAGGCAGUGCCCUGAGCACGAAGUUCGGGCCCAGGCCCGUGGUGAUGACUGGAGGCAUCUUGGCUGCGCUGGGGAUGCUGCUCGCCUCUUUUGCUACUUCCUUGACCCACCUAUACCUGAGUAUUGGGUUGCUGUCAGGCUCUGGCUGGGCUUUGACCUUCGCUCCGACCCUGGCCUGCCUGUCCUGUUAUUUCUCUCGCCGACGAUCCCUGGCCACCGGGCUGGCACUGACAGGCGUGGGCCUCUCCUCCUUCACAUUUGCCCCCUUUUUCCAGUGGCUGCUCAGCCACUACGCCUGGAGGGGGUCCCUGCUGCUGGUGUCUGCCCUCUCCCUCCACCUAGUGGCCUGUGGUGCUCUCCUCCGCCCACCCUCCCUGGCUGAGGACCCUGCUGUGGGUGGUCCCAGGGCCCAACUCACCUCUCUCCUCCAUCAUGGCCCCUUCCUCCGUUACACUGUUGCCCUCACCCUGAUCAACACUGGCUACUUCAUUCCCUACCUCCACCUGGUGGCCCAUCUCCAGGACCUGGAUUGGGACCCACUACCUGCUGCCUUCCUACUCUCAGUUGUUGCUAUUUCUGACCUCGUGGGGCGUGUGGUCUCCGGAUGGCUGGGAGAUGCAGUCCCAGGGCCUGUGACACGACUCCUGAUGCUCUGGACCACCUUGACUGGGGUGUCACUAGCCCUGUUCCCUGUAGCUCAGGCUCCCACAGCCCUGGUGGCUCUGGCUGUGGCCUACGGCUUCACAUCAGGGGCUCUGGCCCCACUGGCCUUCUCCGUGCUGCCUGAACUAAUAGGGACUAGAAGGAUUUACUGUGGCCUGGGACUGUUGCAGAUGAUAGAGAGCAUCGGGGGGCUGCUGGGGCCUCCUCUCUCAGGCUACCUCCGGGAUGUGACAGGCAACUACACGGCUUCUUUUGUGGUGGCUGGGGCCUUCCUUCUUUCAGGGAGUGGCAUUCUCCUCACCCUGCCCCACUUCUUCUGCUUCUCAACUACUACCUCCGGGCCCCAGGACCUUGUAACAGAAGCACUAGAUACUAAAGUUCCCCUACCCAAGGAGGGGCUGGAAGAGGACUGAACUCCACAGAGUCAGGCCCAGAAAGCCAAAGCUUGACAGCUCCAGGUCUUCUCUUGCCACGUCUUGGUCUCCACAGAACCACAGUGCCUUAAGAUUCUUGAUCUGCCUCCCCCUAGAGCAGGCCUGGGGCUCCUGCAAUGUGUGUGCCAACCCUU